ACUGGACCCAGCCCUUAGCAACGGCCUGGCAACGGUUUCCCUGCUGCUGCAGCCCCCGUCGGCUCCUCUUUUCCAGUCCUCCACUGCCGGGGCUGGGCCCGGCCGCGGGAAGGACCGAAGGGGAUACAGCGUGUCCCUGCGGCGGCUGCAAGAGGACUAAGCAUGGAUGGCAGCCGGAGAGUCAGAGCAACCUCUGUCCUUCCCAGAUAUGGUCCACCGUGCCUAUUUAAAGGACACUUGAGCACCAAAAGUAAUGCUUUUUGCACUGACUCCUCUUCUCUCAGACUAAGCACUCUCCAGCUGGUCAAGAAUCACAUGGCUGUUCACUAUAAUAAAAUCCUUUCAGCCAAAGCUGCAGUAGACUGCUCGGUUCCAGUAAGCGUGAGUACCAGCAUAAAGUAUGCAGACCAACAACGAAGAGAGAAACUCAAAAAGGAAUUAGCACAAUGUGAAAAAGAGUUCAAAUUAACUAAAACUGCAAUGCGAGCCAAUUAUAAAAAUAAUUCCAAGUCACUUUUUAAUACCUUACAAAAGCCCUCAGGCGAACCGCAAAUUGAGGAUGACAUGUUAAAAGAAGAAAUGAAUGGAUUUUCAUCCUUUGCAAGGUCACUAGUACCCUCUUCAGAGAGACUACACCUAAGUCUACAUAAAUCCAGUAAAGUCAUCACAAAUGGUCCUGAGAAGAACUCCAGUUCCUCCCCGUCCAGUGUGGAUUAUGCAGCCUCCGGGCCCCGGAAACUGAGCUCUGGAGCCCUGUAUGGCAGAAGGCCCAGAAGCACAUUCCCAAAUUCCCACCGGUUUCAGUUAGUCAUUUCGAAAGCACCCAGUGGGGAUCUUUUGGAUAAACAUUCUGAACUCUUUUCUAACAAACAAUUGCCAUUCACUCCUCGCACUUUAAAAACAGAAGCAAAAUCUUUCCUGUCACAGUAUCGCUAUUAUACACCUGCCAAAAGAAAAAAGGAUUUUACAGAUCAACGGAUAGAAGCUGAAACCCAGACUGAAUUAAGCUUUAAAUCUGAGUUGGGGACAGCUGAGACUAAAAACAUGACAGAUUCAGAAAUGAACAUAAAGCAGGUAGCAUCUAAUUGUGUGACAUAUGAUGCCAAAGAAAAAAUAGCUCCUUUACCUUUAGAAGGGCAUGACUCAACAUGGGAUGAGAUUAAGGAUGAUGCUCUUCAGCAUUCCUCACCAAGGGCAAUGUGUCAGUAUUCCCUGAAGCCCCCUUCAACUCGUAAAAUCUACUCUGAUGAAGAAGAACUGUUGUAUCUGAGUUUCAUUGAAGAUGUAACAGAUGAAAUUUUGAAACUUGGUUUAUUUUCAAACAGGUUUUUAGAACGACUGUUCGAGCGACAUAUAAAACAAAAUAAACAUUUGGAGGAGGAAAAAAUGCGCCACCUGCUGCAUGUCCUGAAAGUAGACUUAGGCUGCACAUCGGAGGAAAACUCGAUUCCAGAUGCUGCUACUACUGGUCCGAAAACAACCCCACUGGAAGAUGAAUAAAGUGGACACAACAAAUAGCAUAUGUUCUACUAUAGAGGUGGCCACAUGAAGAGCUCUGCAAGCCCACUGUGAAAUUGAUAGCAAAUCUUUAUUCAAGUGUAUUAAUUGACCCACAAAUAUCCUGAUUAAUGAAGCUGGCUAGUUUGGCAAGAUGCAUUCUAACUCUUAAAGUGAUUGAUUACUGUGGAGAUGUGUGAUGACAGAUUGGCACCUACUAAGGAAACCUCUCUUGCCUGGUACAUUAUUAAAAAUAAUCCAGUGGGGAAAUAGGACUAAUUUAAUUACAUGCCUUUAUGCAGUAAGAUCCACAGUUGAAAAAUAGAGGCAGUAGCUUUAAUUGCACUGUAAUGUUCACACACAAAUCAUAUCUUGCUUGAAACAGUUUUAUGGCAAAAAUAGACCAUAUAUUGAUUUCACAUAUAUAACAUUUAACCCUUCAAGCCUUUUUGCCCAUUAAAUAUACACACCUUUACAAACCAAUAACAGUUUAGAAGAAUUAAGCUCUUCUGAUUAUAAACUUUUACAUUAUUGAUCAGACAGUAGCACAUAAAAUUGCUUUUUUUUUUAGUAUUUUACAUGAAUAAUUUUAUUUGUGCUUCAUGAAAACUCCAUUUAUCCCAUUUUUUAUUAUACUUUAAGUUUUAGGGUACAUGUGCACAAUGUGCAGGUUUGUUACAUAUGUAUACACGUGCCGUGUUGGUGUGCUGCACCCAUUAACUCAUCAUUUACAUUAGGUAUAUCUCCUAAUGCUAUCCCUCCCCCUCCCCCCACCCCACAACAGGCCCUGGUGUGUGAUGUUCCCCUUCCUGUGUCCAUGUGUUCUCAUUGUUCAGUUCCCACCUAUGAGUGAGAACAUGCAGUGUUUGGUUUUUUGUCCUUGCGAUAGUUUGCUGAGAAUGAUGGUUUCCAGCUUCAUCCAUGUCCCUACAAAGGACAUGAACUCAUCAUUUUUUAUGGCUGCAUAGUAUUCCAUGGUGUAUAUGUGCCACAUUUCCUUAAUCUAGUCUAUCAUUGAUGGACAUUUGGGUUGGUUCCAAGUCUUUGCUAUUAUGAAUAGUGCUGCAAUAAACAUGUGUGCAUGUGUCUUUAUAGCAGCAUGUUUUAUAAUCCUUUGGGUAUAUACCCAGUAAUGGGGUGGCUGGGUCAAAUGAUAUUUCUAGUUCUAGAUCCCUGAGGAAUCGCCACACUGACUUCCACAAUGGUUGAACUAGUUUACAGUCCCACCAACAGUGUAAAAGUGUUCCUAUUUCUCCACAUCCUCUCCAGCACCUGUUGUUUCCUGACUUUUUAAUGACUGCCAUUCUAACUGGUGUGAGAUGGUAUCUCAUUGUGGUUUUGAUUUGCAUUUCUCUGAUGGCCAGUGAUGAUGAGCAUUUUUUCAUGUGUCUUUUGGCUGCAUAAAUGUCUUCUUUUGAGAAGUGUCUGUUCAUAUCCUUCGCCCACUUGUUGAUGGGGUUGUUUGUUUUUUUCUUGUAAAUUUGUUAGAGUUCUUUGUAGAUUCUGGAUAUUAGCCCUUUGUCAGAUGAGUAGAUUGCAAAAAUUUUCUCCCAUUCUGUAGGUUGUCUGUUCACUCUGAUGGUAGUUUCUUUUGCUGUGCAGAAGCUCUUUAGUUUAAUUAGAUCCCAUUUGUCAAUUUUGGCUUUUGUUGCCAUUGCUUUUGGUGUUUUAGACAUGAAGUCCUUGCCCAUACCUAUGUCCUGAAAGGUAUUGCCUAGGUUUUCUUCUAGGGUUUUUACGGUUUUAGGUCUAACAUUUAAGUCUUUAGUCCAUCUUGAAUUAAUUUUUAUAUAAGGUGUAAGGAAGGGAUCCAGUUUCAGCUUUCUACAUAUGGCUAGCAAGGUUUCCCAGCACCAUUUAUUAAAUAGGGAAUGCUUUCCCCAUUUGUUGUUUUUGUCAGGUUUGUCAAAGAUCAGAUGGUUGUAGAUGUGUGGUAUUAUUUCUGAGGGCUCUGUUCUGUUCCAUUGGUCUAUAUCUCUGUUUUGGUACCAGUACCAUGCUGUUUUGGUUACUAUAGCCUUGUAGUAUAAUUUGAAGUCAGGUAACAUGAUGCCUCCAGCUUUGUUCUUUUGGCUUAGGAUUGUCUUGGCAAUGCGGGCCCUUUUUUGGUUCCAUAUGAACUUUAAAGUAGUUUUUUCCAGUUCUGUGAAGAAAGUCAUUGGUAGCUUGAUGAGGGUGGCAUUGAAUCUAUAAAUUACCUUGGGCACUAUGGCCAUUUUCAUGAUAUUGAUUCUUCCUAUCCAUGGGCAUGGAAUGUUCUUGCAUUUGUUUGUGUCUUCUUUUAUUUCAUUGAGCAGUGGUUUGUAGUUCUCCUUGAAGAGGUUCUUCACAUCCCUUGUAAGUUGGAUUCCUAGGUAUUUUAUUCUCUUUGAAGCAACUGUGAAUGGGAGUUCACUCAUGAUGUGGCUCUCUGUUCGUCUGUGAUUUGUGUAUAAGAAUGCUUGUGAUUUUUUGCACAUUGAUUUUGUAUCCAGAGACUUUGCUGAAGUUGCUUAUCAGCUUAAGGAGAUUUUGGGCUGAGACGAUGGGGUUUUUUAAAUAUACAAUCAUGUCAUCUGCACACAGGGACAAUUUGACUUCCUCUUUUCCUAAUUGAAUACCCUUUAUUUCUUUCUCCUGCCUAAUUGCCCUGGCCAGAACUUCCAACACUGUGUUGAAUAGGAGUGGUGAGAGAGGGCAUCUUUGUCUUGUGCCAGUUUUCAAAGGGAAUGCUUCCAGGUUUUGCCCAUUCAGUAUGAUAUUGGCUGUGGGUUUGUCAUAAAUAGCUCUUAUUAUUUUGAGAUACAUCCCAUCAAUACCUAAUUUAUUGAGAGUUUUUAGCAUGAAGGGCUGUUGAAUUUUCUCAAAGGCCUUUUCUGCAUCUAUUGAGAUAAUCAUGUGGUUUUUGUCUUUGGUUCUCUUUAUAUGCUGGAUUACAUUUAUUGAUUUGCAUAUGUUGAACCAGCCUUGCAUCCCAGGGAUGAAGCCCACUUGAUCAUGGUGGAUAAGCUUUUUGAUGUGCUGCUGGAUUCGGUUUGCCAGUAUUUUAUUGAGGAUUUUUGCAUCAAUGUUCAUCAGGGAUAUUGGUCUAAAAUUCUCUUUUUUUGUUGUGUCUUUGUCAGGCUUUGGUAUCAGGAUGAUGCUGGCCUCAUAAAAUGAGUUAGGGAGGAUUCCCUCUUUUUCUAUGGAUUGGAAUAGUUUCAGAAGGAAUGGUACCAGCUUCUUGUACCUCUAGUAGAAUUCGGCUGUGAAUCCAUCUGGUCCUGGACUUUUUUUGGUUGGUAGGCUAUUAAUUAUUGCCUCAAUUUCAGAUCCUGUUAUUGGUCUAUUCAGAGAUUCAACUUCUUCCUGGUUUAGUCUUGGGAGAGUGUAUGUGUCGAGGAAUUUAUCCAUUUCUUCUAGAUUUUCUAGUUUAUUUGCUUAGAGAUGUUUAUAGUAUUCUCUGAUGGUAGCUUGUAUUUCUGUGAGAUCAGUGGUGAUAUCCCCUUCAUCAUUUUUUUAUUGCCUCUAUUUGAUUCUCCCCUCUUUUCUUCUUUAUUAGUCUUGCUAGCAGUCUAUCAAUUUUGUUGAUCUUUUCAAAAAACGAGCCCCUGGAUUCAUUGAUUUUUUGAAGGGUUUUUUGUGUAUCUCCUUCAGUUGUGCUCUGAUCUUAGUUAUUUCUUGCCUUCUGCUAGCUUUUGAAUGUGUUUGCUCUUGCUUCUCUAGUUCUUUUAAUUGUGAUGUUAGGGUGUCAAUUUUACAUCUUUCCUGCUUUCUCUUAUGGGCAUUUAGUGCUAUAAAUUUCCCUCUACACACUGCUUUAAAUGUGUCCCAGAGAUUCUGGUAUGUUGUGUCUUUGUUCUCACUGGUUUCAAAGAACAUCUUUAUUUCUGCCUUAAUUUUGUUAUAUACCCAUUAGUCAUUCAGGAGAAGGUUGUUCAGUUUCCAUGUAGUUGAGCGGUUUUGAGUGAGUUUCUUAAUCCUGAGUUCUACUUUGAUUGCACUGUGGUCUGAGAGACAGUUUGUUAUAAUUUCUGUUCUUUUACAUUUGCUGAGGAGUGCUUUACUUCCAGCUAUGUGGUCAAUUUUGGAAUAAGGGCAAUGUGGUGCUGAGAAGAAUGUAUAUUCUGUUGAUUUGUGGUGGAGAGUUCUGUAGAUGUCUAUUAGGUCUGCUUGGUGCAGAGCUGAGUUCAAUUCCUGGAUAUCCUUGUUAACUUUCUGUCUCGUUUAUCUGUCUAAGGUUGACAGUGGGGUGUUAAAGUCUCCCAUUAUUAUUGUGUGGGAGUCUAAGUCUCUUUGUAAGUCUCUAAGGACUUGCUUUAUGAAUCUAGGUGCUCCUGUAUUGGGUGCAUAUAUGUUUAGGAUAAUUAGCUCUUCUUGUUGAAUUGAUCCCUUUACCAUUAUGUAAUGGCCUUGUCUCUUUUGAUCUUUGUUGGUUUAAAGUCUGUUUUAUCAGAGACUAGGAUUGCAACCCCUGCCUUUUUUUUCCAUUUGCUUGGUAGAUCUUCCUCCAUCCCUUUGUUUUGAGCCUAUGUGAGUCUCUGCAUGUGAGAUGGGUCUCCUGAAUACAGCACACUGAUGGGUCUUGACUCUUUAUCCGUUUUGCCAGUCUGUGUAUUUUAAUUGAAGCAUUUAGCCCAUUUACAUUUAAGGUUAAUAUUGUUAUGUGUGAACUUGAUCCUGUCAUUAUGAUGUUAGCUGGUUAUUUUGCUCAUUAGUUGAUGCAGUUUCUUCCUAGCAUUGAUGGUCUUUACAUUUUGGCAUGUUUUUGCAGUGGCUGGUACCAGUCGUUCCUUUCCAUGUUUACUGCUUCUUUCAGGAGCUCUUGUAGAGCAGGCCUGGUGGUGACAAAAUCUCUCAGCAUUUGCUUGUCUGUAAAGGAUUUUAUUUCUCCUUCACUUAUGAAGCUUAAUUUGGCUGGAUAUGAAAUUCUGGGUUGAAAAUUCGUUUAAGAAUGUUGAAUAUUGGCCCCCACUCUCUUCUGGCUUGUAGAGUUUCUGCUGAGAUUCGCCGUUAGUCUGAUGGUCUUCCCUUUGUGGGUAACCCGACCUUUCUCUCUGGCUGCCCUUAACAUUUUUUCCUUCAUUUCAACUUUGGUGAAUCUGACAAUUAUGUGUCUUGGAGUUGCUCUUCUCGAGGAUUAUCUUUAUGGCAUUCUCUGUAUUUCCUGAAUCUGAAUGUUGGCCUGCCUUGCUAGGUUGGGGAAGUUCUCCUGGAUAAUAUCCUGCAGAGUGUUUUCCAACUUGGUUCCAUUCUCCCCAUCACUUUCAGGUACACCAAUCAGACAUAAAUUUGGUCUUUUCACAUAGUCCCAUAUUUCUUGGAGGCUUUGUUCAUUUCCUUUUACUCUUUUUUCUCUAAACUUCUCUUCUUGCUUCAUUUCAUUCAUUUGAUCUUCAAUCACUGAUACCCUUUCUUCCAGUUGAUCGAAUCGGCUACUGAAGCUUGUGCAUUCAUCACGUAGUUCUCUUGCCAUGUUUUUCAGCUCCAUCAGGUCAUUUAAGGACUUCUCUACACUGUUUAUUCUAGUUCGCCAUUCAUCUAAUCUUUUUUCAAGGUUUUUAGCUUCUUUGCAGUGGGUUCAAACUUCCUCCUUUAGCUCAGAGAAGUUUGAUCGUCUGAAGCCUUCUUCUCUCAACUUGUCAAAGUCAUUCUCCAUCCAGCUUUGUUCCGUUGCUGGUAAGGAGCUGCGUUCCUUUGGAGGGGGAGAGGCGCUCUGAUUUUUAGAAUUUUCAGCUUUUCUGCUCUCUUUUUUCCCCAUCUUUGUGGUUUUAUCUAUCUCUGCUCUUUGAUGAUGGUGACGUACAGAUGGGGUUUUGAUGUGGAUGUCCUUUCUGUUUGUUAGUUUUCCUUCUAACAGUCAGGACCCUCAGCUGCAGGUCUGUUGGAGCUUGCUGGAGGUCCACUCCAGACCCUGUUUGCCUGGGUAUCAGCAGCAGAGGCUGCAGAACAGCACAUAUUGCUGAACAGCAAAUGUUGCUGCCUGAUCGUUCCUCUGGAAGCUUCAUCUCAGAGGGGCACCUGGCCAUGUGAGGUGUCAGUCUGCCCCUACUGGGAGGUGCCUCCCAGUUAGGCUACUCGGGGGUCAGGGACCCACUUGAGGGGGCAGUCUGUCCGUUCUCAGAUCUCAAACUCCUUUCUGGGAGAACCACUAUUCACUUCAAAGCUGUCAGACAGGGACAUUUAAGUCUGCAGAGGUUUCUGCUGCCUUUUGUUCGGCUAUGACCUGCCCCCAGAGGUGGAGUCUACAGAGGCAGGCAGGCCUCCUUGAGCUGUGGUGGGCUCCACCCAGUUCGAGCUUCCUGGCUGCUUUGUUUACCUACUCAAGCCUCAGCAAUGGUGGAUGCCCCUCCCCCAGCCUCGCUGCCAUCUUGCAGAUAGAUCUCAGACCGCUGUGCUAGCAGUGAGUGAGUAUCUGUGGGCGUGGGACCCUCCGAGCCAGGUGUGGGAUAUAAUCUCCUGGUGUGCCGUUUGCUAAGACCAUUGGAAAAGCUCAGUAUUUGGGUGGGAAUUACCUGAUUUUCCAGGUGCCAUCUGUUACCACUUCCCUUGGCUAGGAAAGGGAAUUCCCUGACCCCUUGCACUUCCCGGCUGAGGCGAUGCCUCACCCUGCUUUGGCUUACGCUCGGUGGGCUGCACCCACUGUCCUGCCCCCACUGUCCGACAAGCCCCGUGAGAUGAACCCGGUACCUCAGUUGGAAAUGCAGAAAUCACCUGUCUUCUGCGUCACUCGCGCUGGGAGCUGUAGACUGGAGCUGUUCCUAUUUGGCUAUCUUGGAACCGCAAACAGUAUGUUUUUCUUACAUUUUUUCCUUUACCUUUUUGUUUGACUUACAGGGGUUUAAGUAUUCUGUAUUAUCUUGUUUUUAUUAAACCUGUUCUAGAAAUAAACUUGUUGUCUCUGGAGAAUA